ACACAGUGCUGAGGCAGAACGCAGGUUCGUCACAGUGGGCCUCCGUGGGCGGCGCCGCACGCUCGUCACAGUGGGCCUCCGCCGGCUACGCCGCUGCUUCAGUGGCUUGCAGGCACUUUCCUCUUGGAAGUGGCGACUGCUGCGGGGCUGAGCGGUGCUCGCACGCGUCUCGGGAGCCAGGUUGGCGGCGCGAUGAGGCGCAGCAAGGCCGAUGUGGAGCGGUACGUCGCCUCGGUGCUGGGUCUCACCCCGUCGCCUCGACAGAAGUCAAUGAAAGGAUUCUAUUUUGCAAAGCUGUAUUAUGAAGCUAAAGAAUAUGAUCUUGCUAAAAAAUACAUAUGUACUUACAUUAAUGUGCAAGAGAGGGAUCCCAAAGCUCACAGAUUUCUGGGUCUUCUUUAUGAAUUGGAAGAAAACACAGAGAAAGCCGUUGAAUGUUACAGGCGUUCAGUGGAAUUAAACCCAACACAAAAAGAUCUUGUGUUGAAGAUUGCAGAAUUGCUUUGUAAAAAUGAUGUUACUGAUGGAAGAGCAAAAUACUGGGUCGAAAGAGCAGCAAAACUUUUCCCAGGAAGUCCUGCAAUUUAUAAACUAAAGGAACAGCUUCUAGAUUGUGAAGGUGAAGAUGGAUGGAAUAAACUUUUUGACUUGAUUCAGUCAGAACUUUAUGUAAGACCUGAUGACGUCCAUGUGAACAUCCGGCUAGUGGAGUUGUAUCGCUCAACUAAAAGAUUGAAGGAUGCUGUGGCCCACUGCCAUGAGGCAGAGAGGAACAUAGCUUUGCGUUCAAGUUUAGAGUGGAAUUCGUGUGUUGUACAGACCCUUAAGGAAUAUCUGGAGUCUUUACAGUGUUUGGAGUCUGAUAAAAGUGACUGGCGAGCAACCAAUACAGACUUACUGCUGGCCUAUGCUAAUCUUAUGCUUCUUACGCUUUCCACUAGAGAUGUGCAGGAAAAUAGAGAAUUACUGGAAAGUUUUGAUAGUGCUCUUCAGUCUGCGAAAUCUUCUUUGGGUGGAAAUGAUGAACUGUCAGCUACUUUCUUAGAAAUGAAAGGACAUUUCUAUAUGUAUGCUGGUUCUCUGCUCUUGAAGAUGGGUCAGCAUGGUAAUAAUGUUCAAUGGCGAGCUCUUUCUGAGCUGGCUGCAUUGUGCUAUCUCAUAGCAUUUCAGGUUCCAAGACCAAAGAUUAAAUUAAGAGAAGGUAAAGCUGGACAAAAUCUGCUGGAAAUGAUGGCCUGUGACCGACUGAGCCAAUCAGGGCACAUGUUGCUAAGCUUAAGUCGUGGCAAGCAAGAUUUCUUAAAAGAGGUUGUUGAAACUUUUGCCAACAAAAUUGGGCAGUCUGCGUUAUAUGAUGCUCUGUUUUCUAGUCAGUCACCUAAGGAUACAUCUUUUCUUGGUAGCGAUGAUAUUGGAAAAAUUGAUGUACAAGAACCAGAGCUUGAAGAUUUGGCUAGAUACGAUGUUGGUGCUAUUCGAGCACAUAAUGGUAGUCUUCAGCAUCUUACUUGGCUUGGCUUACAGUGGAAUUCAUUGCCUGCUUUACCUGGAAUCCGAAAAUGGCUAAAACAGCUUUUCCAUCGUUUGCCCCAUGAAACCUCAAGGCUUGAAACAAAUGCGCCUGAAUCAAUAUGUAUUUUAGAUCUUGAAGUAUUUCUCCUUGGAGUAGUAUAUACCAGCCACUUACAAUUAAAGGAGAAAUGUAAUUCUCACCAUAGCUCCUAUCAGCCGUUAUGCCUGCCCUUUCCUGUGUGUAAACAGCUUUGUACAGAAAGACAAAAAUCUUGGUGGGAUGCGGUUUGUACUCUGAUUCACAGAAAAGCAGUACCUGGAAACUUGGCAAAAUUGAGACUUCUAGUUCAGCAUGAAAUAAACACUCUAAGAGCCCAGGAAAAACAUGGCCUUCAACCUGCUCUGCUUGUACAUUGGGCAAAAUACCUUCAGAAAACGGGCAGCGGUCUUAAUUCUUUUUAUGGUCAACUAGAAUACAUAGGGAGAAGUGUUCAUUAUUGGAAGAAAGUUUUGCCAUUGUUGAAGAUAAUAAAGAAGAACAGUAUUCCUGAACCUAUUGAUCCUCUGUUUAAACAUUUUCAUAGUGUAGACAUUCAGGCAUCAGAAAUUGUUGAAUAUGAAGAAGACGCACACAUAACUUUUGCUAUAUUGGAUGCAGUAAAUGGAAAUAUAGAAGAUGCUGUGACUGCUUUUGAAUCUAUAAAAAGUGUUGUUUCUUAUUGGAAUCUUGCACUGAUUUUUCACAGGAAGGCAGAAGACAUUGAAAAUGAUGCCCUUUCUCCUGAAGAACAAGAAGAAUGCAGAAAUUAUCUGACAAAGACCAGGGACUACCUAAUAAAGAUUAUAGAUGACGGUGAUUCAAAUCUUUCAGUGGUCAAGAAAUUGCCUGUGCCCCUGGAGUCUGUAAAACAGAUGCUUAAUUCAGUCAUGCAGGAACUCGAAGACUAUAGUGAAGGAGGUCCUCUCUAUAAAAAUGGUUCUUUGCGAAAUGCAGAUUCAGAAAUAAAACAUUCUACACCGUCUCCUACCAAAUAUUCACUAUCACCAAGUAAAAGUUACAAGUAUUCUCCCGAAACACCACCUCGAUGGACAGAAGAUCGGAAUUCUUUACUGAAUAUGAUUUGCCAACAAGUAGAGGCCAUUAAGAAAGAAAUGCAGGAGUUGAAACUAAAUAGCAGUAAGUCAGCAUCCCGUCAUCGUUGGCCCACAGAGAAUUAUGGACCAGACUCGGUGCCUGAUGGAUAUCAGGGGUCACAGACAUUUCAUGGGGCUCCACUAACAGUUGCAACUACUGGCCCUUCAGUAUAUUAUAGUCAGUCACCAGCAUAUAAUUCCCAGUAUCUUCUCAGACCAGCAGCUAAUGUUACUCCCACAAAGGGUUCUUCUAAUACAGAAUUUAAGUCAACCAAAGAAGGAUUUUCCAUCCCUGUGUCUGCUGAUGGAUUUAAAUUUGGCAUUUCGGAACCAGGAAAUCAAGAAAAGAAAAGGGAAAAGCCUCUUGAAAAUGAUACUGGCUUACAGGCUCAGGAUAUUAGGGGCCGGAAGAAGGGCCGUGGUGUGAUUUUUGGCCAAACAAGUAGCACUUUUACAUUUGCAGAUGUUGCAAAAUCAACUUCAGGAGAAGGAUUUCAGUUUGGCAAAAAAGACCUCAAUUUCAAGGGAUUUUCAGGUGCUGGAGAAAAAUUAUUCUCAUCACGAUACGGUAAAAUGGCCAAUAAAGCAAACACUUCCGGUGACUUUGAGAAAGAUGAUGAUGCCUAUAAGACUGAGGACAGCGAUGACAUCCAUUUUGAACCAGUAGUUCAAAUGCCUGAAAAAGUAGAACUUGUAACAGGAGAAGAAGGUGAAAAAGUUCUGUAUUCACAGGGGGUAAAACUAUUUAGAUUUGAUGCUGAGGUAAGGCAGUGGAAAGAAAGGGGCUUGGGGAACUUAAAAAUUCUCAAAAACGAGGUCAAUGGCAAACUAAGAAUGCUGAUGCGAAGAGAACAAGUACUAAAAGUGUGUGCUAAUCAUUGGAUAACGACUACAAUGAACCUGAAGCCCCUCUCUGGAUCAGAUAGAGCAUGGAUGUGGUCAGCCAGUGAUUUCUCUGAUGGUGAUGCCAAACUAGAGCGGUUGGCAGCAAAAUUUAAAACACCAGAGCUGGCUGAAGAAUUCAAGCAGAAAUUUGAGGAAUGCCAGCGGCUUCUGUUAGACAUACCACUUCAAACUCCCCAUAAACUUGUAGAUACUGGCAGAGCUGCCAAGUUAAUACAGAGAGCUGAAGAAAUGAAGAGUGGACUGAAAGAUUUCAAAACAUUUUUGACAAAUGAUCAAACAAAAGUCACUGAGGAAGAAAAUAAGGGUUCAGGUACAGGUGUGGCCGGUGCCUCAGACACAACAAUAAAACCCAAUGCUGAAAACACUGGGCCCACAUUAGAAUGGGAUAACUAUGACUUAAGGGAAGAUGCUUUGGAUGAUAGUGUCAGUAGUAGCUCAGUACAUGCUUCUCCAUUGGCAAGUAGCCCUGUGAGAAAAAAUCUUUUCCGCUUUGAUGAGUCAACAACAGGAUCUAACUUCAGUUUUAAAUCUGCUUUGAGUCUAUCUAAGUCUCCUGCCAAGUUGAAUCAGAGUGGGACUUCAGUUGGCACUGAUGAAGAAUCUGUUGUUACUCAAGAAGAAGAGAGAGAUGGACAGUACUUUGAACCUGUUGUUCCUUUACCUGAUCUAGUUGAAGUAUCCAGUGGUGAGGAAAAUGAACAAGUUGUUUUUAGUCACAGGGCAGAAAUCUACAGAUAUGAUAAAGAUGUUGGUCAAUGGAAAGAAAGGGGCAUUGGUGAUAUAAAGAUUUUACAGAAUUAUGAUAAUAAGCAAGUUCGUAUAGUGAUGAGAAGGGACCAAGUAUUAAAACUUUGUGCCAAUCACAGAAUAACUCCAGACAUGAGUUUGCAAAAUAUGAAAGGGACAGAAAGAGUAUGGGUGUGGACUGCAUGUGAUUUUGCAGAUGGAGAAAGAAAAGUAGAGCAUUUAGCUGUUCGUUUUAAACUACAGGAUGUUGCAGACUCGUUUAAGAAAAUUUUUGAUGAAGCAAAAACAGCCCAGGAAAAAGAUUCUUUGAUAACACCUCAUGUUUCUCGGUCAAGCACUCCCAGAGAGUCACCAUGUGGCAAAAUUGCUGUAGCUGUAUUAGAAGAAAUCACAAGAGAGAGGACAGAUGUUAUUCAGGGUGAUGAUGUAGCAGAUGCAGCUUCAGAAGUUGAAGUGUCUAGCACAUCUGAAACAACAACAAAAGCAGUGGUUUCUCCUCCAAAGUUUGUAUUUGUUUCAGAGUCUGUUAAAAGAAUUUUUAGUAGUGAAAAAUCAAAACCAUUUGCAUUUGGCAACAGUUCUGCCACUGGGUCUUUGUUUGGAUUUAGUUUUAAUGCACCUUUGAAAAGUAACAAUAGUGAAACUAGUUCAGUAGCCCAGAGUGGAUCUGAAAGCAAAGUGGAACCUAAAAAAUGUGAACUGUCAAAGAACUCUGAUAUCGAACAGUCUUCAGAUAGCAAAGUCAAAAAUCUCUCUGCUUCCUUUCCAACGGAAGAAUCUUCAAUCAACUACACAUUUAAAACACCAGAAAAGGCAAAAGAGAAGAAAAAACCUGAAGAUUCUCCCUCAGAUAGUCUCGGUCUCCUGACCUCGUGAUCCACCCGCCUCGGCCUCCCAAAGUGCUGGGAUUACAGGCAUGAGCCACUGCGCCUGGCUGACACAUGUCUUAAUUCUGGUAUUCACCAGAUUUGUUUCGUGUUCUCCGUUGUUAGUCAUCAAAUUUGUCUACUUUUUAAAUAGAAACAUUAGCUAGAGCAAGGAACUUAGAAACACUCAAGCGGCACUGAAUGUGUAGAAUUGCAUAACCAAUAUAGCUUCUUUGCUUUCACAUUUACAAUUAGUUGGAGUUUUAGUUCAGCCGUACCCAGUAUCUUCCAUUCUGCUUCCAGGAAGAAAUGGAAAAAUGUCAGCCAUGAUGAUGCAGUAUUUUAGUAGCAAGUUGAUGGUGUUUUGGUUUCCCAUGGGAAAUAUUGUCACUGGAGCAUUAGCAGCUAUCGGUCACUUAUUAGGGUAAAAAAGCAACUUCAGAAGAAUUUAAUAUAUGCCAAAGAAUCAACAAAGGAAGUAAUCAGCCAGGGCAAAGGUCGCACAAGAGAUUGUAAUCUAGCAAUCAGCAGUGGAAUAAGCAGUCAGCUUACCAGAAACCCAGGAAAAUGCUUCAGAAAGGGCAGUCAGGACUAAGGCAAUUUAAUGAAAUGCAAAAUAAAUGAAAUCUGAAGUUUAAAUAAAAAUCUAGAUUACAAUUCUGGUUUCUAACUCAGUUAUGAGACCUUGGGCAAAGUCAUUAAAUUUCUCUGAACUUCAGAUUUUUGGGAGUCAAUAAACCAAUACAUGUCAAAGGGCCUGGUAAACUUUACAGUUUAGACCAGGCGUGGUGUCUCACCCCUGCAAUCUGAGCACUUUGGGAGCCAAAGCAGUUGGAUCACAUGAGGCCAGGAGUUUGAGACCAGUCUGAACAACAUGGUGAAAUCCCAUCUCUAUUAAAAGUACAAAAAUUAUCUGGGCGGGAUGGCAUGCACCUGGAAGUCCCAGCUACUUGUGGGGCUGAGGUGGGAGGAUGGCCUGAGCCUGGGAGGCAGAGGUUGCUGUGAGCCAAGAUCGUGCCACUGCACUCCAACCUGUGUGACAGAGUGAGACCCUGUCUCAGAAAAAAUAACACUUUACAGUUUAUCAGCAAACAGGAAAGUCUUGCUAGGCAAUGUAAUUGAUUAGUUCCGUGCCCUGGAUUCUGGGCUCUUAACUGUAUGAGCACUGUAGGUGUGAGCAGCAACAAUUAAGAAGCUGCAGAGGUAAAGGUAUAAGGGCAGUGAUUGAGGAUGUCUACCAAGCAGAUUUCAGCAAGUGUGUUUCAAGAAGUAUGCAGCAAUCUGAAAUACCUAAUCCUGAAAAAUUUCUAGAAUCUAGUCUUUUAAUUUUGGCCAGUAUUUAGCAGUAGUUUGGCCCUCUACUCUAAAUUAAUAAAAAAUAAGUAGUACUAUAUUAUGAGCUGUGUUAUCUAACAGUUUAUCUUAGCUAGUAGCAAUUAAUUUAUAGCUGCUAUUAAAAUGACUAACGUAGUUAAAAGUUUGAUGAGUAAGUUUUUUUUUGUUGUUUUUUUUUUUUGAGCUGGCGUCUCGCUCUGUCGCCAGGCUGGAGUGCGGUGGCGUGAUCUUGGCUCACUGCAACCUCCGCCUCCUGGUUUCCAGCAAUUCUCUGCCUCAGCCUCCCCAGCAGCUGGGAUUACAGGCACCUGCCACUGUGCCUGGCUAAUUUUUGUAUUUUUAGUAGAGAUAGGGUUUCACCAUCUUGGCCAGGCUGGUCUUGAACUUGCUGACCUCGUGAUCCACCCACCUUAGCCUCCCAAACUGCUAGGAUUACAGAUUUGAGCCACCACGCCCGGCCUUGAUGACUAAAUUUUAAGAAAUGUUUUAGCAAUUCUUCAUACACCUUUCACUUAUAGUUACUUAAUUCCUCUACUCUUAUCAUUUGAUAUUUUCAUUUUAUUGUGUACCUCUGUAAGGCCGAAUCAAUAGAUUUUGAACAAUCUCACACUUAACCUUUAAAAAAAAUCUAAUAGGCCCAGUUUCCUCUCAACAAUCUUUGAAGAACCUUCGAGAAAGGAGAAACACAGACCUCCCGCUUCUAGACAUGCACACUGUAACCCGGGAAGAGGGAGAAGGCAUGGAGACAACUGAUACGGAGUCUGUGUCUUCCGCCAGCACAUACACACAGUCUUUAGAGCAGCUGCUUAAUUCUCCCGAAACUAAACUUGGUCUGUUACUCUGUCUAAAUAUGUUCUUCUUCUUUAAUUUCACUGUCUUAUUUAAUUACUAUUACUCUAAGGUACAUAUGCUUUUUUGGGCUGCUCCAAUAAAAUUUCUUUCAAUAUUCCACUA